GUGGUAGAAGUUGCCAGGGACAGAUAACAUGGCAGCCAGCGGGAAGACCAGCAAGUCCGAACCGAACCAUGUUAUCUUCAAGAAGAUCUCCCGGGACAAAUCGGUGACCAUCUACCUGGGGAACAGAGACUACAUAGACCAUGUCAGCCAAGUCCAGCCUGUGGAUGGUGUCGUGUUGGUUGAUCCUGAUCUUGUGAAGGGAAAGAAAGUGUAUGUCACUCUGACCUGCGCCUUCCGCUAUGGCCAAGAGGACAUUGACGUGAUCGGCUUGACCUUCCGCAGGGACCUGUACUUCUCCCGGGUCCAGGUGUAUCCUCCUGUGGGGGCCGCGAGCACCCCCACAAAACUGCAAGAGAGCCUGCUUAAAAAGCUGGGGAGCAACACGUACCCCUUUCUCCUGACGUUUCCUGACUACUUGCCCUGUUCAGUGAUGUUGCAGCCAGCUCCACAAGAUUCAGGGAAGUCCUGUGGGGUUGACUUUGAGGUCAAAGCAUUCGCCACAGACAGCACCGAUGCCGAAGAGGACAAAAUCCCCAAGAAGAGCUCCGUGCGAUUACUGAUCCGCAAAGUACAGCAUGCCCCACUUGAGAUGGGUCCCCAGCCCCGAGCUGAGGCGGCCUGGCAGUUCUUCAUGUCUGACAAGCCCCUGCACCUUGCGGUCUCUCUCAACAAAGAGAUCUAUUUCCAUGGGGAGCCCAUCCCUGUGACCGUGACUGUCACCAAUAACACAGAGAAGACCGUGAAGAAGAUUAAAGCAUUCGUGGAACAGGUGGCCAAUGUGGUUCUCUACUCGAGUGAUUAUUACGUCAAGCCCGUGGCUAUGGAGGAAGCGCAAGAAAAAGUGCCACCAAACAGCACUUUGACCAAGACGCUGACGCUGCUGCCCUUGCUGGCUAACAAUCGAGAAAGGAGAGGCAUUGCCCUGGAUGGGAAAAUCAAGCACGAGGACACAAACCUUGCCUCCAGCACCAUCAUUAAGGAGGGCAUAGACCGGACCGUCCUGGGAAUCCUGGUGUCUUACCAGAUCAAGGUGAAGCUCACAGUGUCAGGCUUUCUGGGAGAGCUCACCUCCAGUGAAGUCGCCACUGAGGUCCCAUUCCGCCUCAUGCACCCUCAGCCUGAGGACCCAGGUAAAUGAAGCAGCAAAAAUAAUAUAGGUGAAAUCUCAGAAAUUCUGAAGAAACAUUCUCUGCAUCGAGGCAGCUUAGUUGACGGGAAAGAAAAACAGAUCUGUCUAAAUGAGAACUCUCCGUAGGUAUAGGAAUAAGGGAUAUUUUAAGUAAAAGUGGUAUAAACAAGCAGGGUUUAUUUUUCUCAUACUUUACAAAUAGCUUUUCUAUAUUGGUAGUGAAAUGCCGUUUAAACAUUAGAAUGAGCCCCCACUAUUCAUUUUAGGUUUUGUCUCAACAGUACUUUGUUUCAAAAUAGCUCUUCCAAAUACUUUGGAUUCAGAUCCUCAAUGAACUUUUCCAAAACUGUCCCUUGGAGAAAAAUGUAGUCCAGCUAUAUGUUUUCAGUUCAUUUAUGCUUGUGUCAUUAAAAUGUUACUUUUUCAUGGUGUGGGAUUAAGAUGCUUUCUGGUUCCUUUCAAGGACAUUAAAAAGAUAGUCACUUGAGGAGAUGUCAUAGUUUAUGUUGGGUUGUUUUCUGGAACUUUGAGUAGACUUUAUGCCUUAAUUUUUUUUUUUUGAGACAUA